GUGCGGAGUUUGGCUGCUCCGGGGUUAGCAGGUGAGCCUGCGAUGCGCGGGAAGACGUUCCGCUUUGAAAUGCAGCGGGAUUUGGUGAGUUUCCCGCUGUCUCCAGCGGUGCGGGUGAAGCUGGUGUCUGCGGGGUUCCAGACUGCUGAGGAACUCCUAGAGGUGAAACCCUCCGAGCUUAGCAAAGAAGUUGGGAUAUCUAAAGCAGAAGCCUUAGAAACUCUGCAAAUUAUCAGAAGAGAAUGUCUCACAAAUAAACCAAGAUAUGCUGGUACAUCUGAGUCACACAAGAAGUGUACAGCACUGGAACUUCUUGAGCAGGAGCAUACCCAGGGCUUCAUAAUCACCUUCUGUUCAGCACUAGAUGAUAUUCUUGGGGGUGGAGUGCCCUUAAUGAAAACAACAGAAAUUUGUGGUGCACCAGGUGUUGGAAAAACACAAUUAUGUAUGCAGUUGGCAGUAGAUGUGCAGAUACCAGAAUGUUUUGGAGGAGUGGCAGGUGAAGCAGUUUUUAUUGAUACAGAGGGAAGUUUUAUGGUUGAUAGAGUGGUAGACCUUGCUACUGCCUGCAUUCAGCACCUUCAGCUUAUAGCAGAAAAACACAAGGGAGAGGAACACCGAAAAGCUUUGGAGGAUUUCACUCUUGAUAAUAUUCUUUCUCAUAUUUAUUAUUUUCGCUGUCGUGACUACACAGAGUUACUGGCACAAGUUUAUCUUCUUCCAGAUUUCCUUUCAGAACACUCAAAGGUUCGACUAGUGAUAGUGGAUGGUAUUGCUUUUCCAUUUCGUCAUGACCUAGAUGACCUGUCUCUUCGUACUCGGUUAUUAAAUGGCCUAGCCCAGCAAAUGAUCAGCCUUGCAAAUAAUCACAGAUUAGCUGUAAUUUUAACCAAUCAGAUGACAACAAAGAUUGAUAGAAAUCAGGCCUUGCUUGUUCCUGCAUUAGGGGAAAGUUGGGGACAUGCUGCUACAAUACGGCUAAUCUUUCAUUGGGACCGAAAGCAAAGCAGGUUGGCAACAUUGUACAAGUCACCCAGCCAGAAGGAAUGCACAGUACUGUUUCAAAUCAAACCUCAGGGAUUUAGAGAUACUGUUGUUACUUCUGCAUGUUCAUUGCAAACAGAAGGUUCCUUGAGCACCCGGAAACGGUCACGAGACCCAGAGGAAGAAUUAUAACCCAGAAACAAAUCUCAAAGUGUACAAAUUUAUUGAUGUUGUGAAAUCAAUGUGUACAAGUGGACUUGUUACCUUAAAGUAUAAAUAAACACACUAUGGCAUGAAUGAAUCCAGAUCAUAUGAAGUGAAUGGGAAAAAUACCUAAAUAUGAUUCUGUGAAAGUUUUUCUAAAGCAGUAUUCUGCAAUUAUAUUUUACCCUGUUUUCAUUUUCAGUAACAUUCAGUAGAGAUGAUUAUUAUAUUUCACAAAUGUGGAAAGCUGAUCUCAUGUGGCCAGUCUGAAUUUACCAUUCAUACUGUUUUCACCCCUUUCUUUCCCAGUUGCCUAUAAAAUCUUAGGAAGAAACAUAUCAUAUUCUUAUUGUGUUUUUUUUUUUUUUUUUUUUUUUGGAGAUGGAUUCUCGCUCUGUAGUCCAGGCUGGAGUGCAAUGGCGCAAUCUCUGCUCACUGCAACCUCCGCCUCCCAGGUUCAAGCGAUUCAUCUGCCUCAGCCUCCCGAGUAGCUGGGGUUACAGGCACCUGCCAUCGUGCCUGGCUAAUUUUUUGUAUUUUUGUAGAGACAGAGUUUUACCAUGUUGGCCAAGCUGGUCUUGAACUCCUGACCUCAGGUGAUCUGCCUGCCCCUGCCUCCCAAAGUGCUGGGAUUACAGUCGUGAGCCACUGUGCCCAGCCAUGUUCUUUUUAAAUGUAAAUUUGAUAAUUCUUUAAAAUUACCCGCUUUUAUAAUUAUAAAAGAGAAGCCAGCACCAUGAGUCAGCAUAUUAUUCUGUUCAGUUUUAUAGGUAAGAUACAAAUUUUAGGUGACCAAACUGAUUUUAGUGACCUCAAUCCUAAAAUCUAAGCCAUUUGUUUAGCUUUUAAUGACAUUUUAUAAUGUUAAAGGGAGGACUUUGGAGCUGUUAUCUCAUCUAGAGAUUGUUUGGAACAUAUGUCUUCCAGAAUAGGUUGAUAAGCUCACAAUCAUUUAUUGCUACGUUUUUGUUUUUGUUUUGAGACAAGGUCUCACUCCGUCACCCAGGCUGGAGUGCAGUGGCAUGAUCAUAGCUCACUGCAGCCUCGACCUCCCGGGCUCAAGCAAUCCUCUCACUUCAGCCUCCUGAGUAGCUGGGACUACAGGGAGGCACUACCAUGCCCUGCUAAUUUUUGGAUUUUUUUGUAGAGACAAGGUCUCACUAUGUUGCCCAGGCUGGUCUCAAACUCCUGGUCUCAAGCGAUCCUCUUGCCUUGUCUUCCCAAAGUGCUGGGAUUACAGAUGUGAGCCACCACACCUGGCCUCAUUUCUAUAUUUUGAAACACGGUAUGAUCCAUUCUAGAAUUCUAGUUGUUAUGUUGACAUUUUUCUUUGAAUAAUCUUAACUUUGCUUAAAUAAAUUAAAGAUUUCAAUUCUC